CCUUCUGGAAUCUUGUAACGGUUCUAACAGCUGGGUGCGGGUGGAGCUGCGGGCGAUCGCCAGCUCGAGUGCAGAUUCCUUGCUGUGACCGAGGUUCAGAGUGAGCUCUGUCGGUGUGUCAGUUUGCCUCUUCAGGCACUCUUCAAUGAAACCUCAUCAGCAGAUCGGGCUCUCUUCCCUUGCCUUGCCUCCUAACCCCCCUAGGCCAGGUGAGGGGGACAGGGUACUGGGAGGUAAGAAGGAACUCUUCUGCAAGGAGGGCUCUCACGUCUGUCUUAGGCCUGCUCCUUACCAGAGUCUUUGGGGAAGCAGUAGGGAGGGCCUGAGGGUCUCAGGAAAGGCUCUCUGCUGGUCUGGCUCUGCUCUGUAGCUCCAUCUAUUUCCCUGUCCCAGGUCCUUUCUUCCUCCUAACCCCAUUGACUCUGACCAUCCCCUGCCCAGAGCCUGAGGUCCCUUCUCUGGCCCCUCUGCUGGGCUGGCCCAUGCAGGUGAGGCCCCGCAUCUGGCAUCCUGGAACUGGCAGUUGGAGCCUGAGCUAUGGGCAAGGUCACUUCGACAGCAGUUGAAUGCCCAGCUCCUCAUGGUCCCGGAGGAGAGGAGGGUAGGUUUGUCUUCUGAUGAGACAUCAUCUGAUUCCCUUAAGUCUUGGCACUCCAUAUGUGUCUUGGACAGCAAAGAACAGCCCUUGGCCUGCCAGCAGAAACAGAGGCAGUUCGUGAAGCCAGUGACUGAGUCAGAGCAGCCCACAGUGCUGGAACUCCUGCUAGCUGAGCUCCGAACUCUGUUCUCAGCUGUGUUGCAGGACAGUAGCCCUGCAGCUUGGCGCUAUCUUCAUGCAGUACUGGGUCUACUGCCUCCAUAUCGUGAGUUGCUAGUUGGCCACCUUGAUUUGCUGCCCUUCCUGGAGCAGCUGUACUGCUGGGCACCCUGGGUCCAAACCCACCUCCAUCUGGACCUGCUAGGUGCCAUUGUCCAGGCCUUUCCUCCAGACAGCUCUUUGUUAGACAGUGCUUCCCAUGCUGACUGCUGUCCCCAGAAGCGGAGGCUCCAUCACAGGCCCCCAUGCCCAGCUUGCCCUUUUGUGCAGGCCCAGUGGAGCAGGCAGCAAGUAAAGGAGGAGCUGGCCACCUGGCUGCGACCAUUGACACUGCCUGAGCUACAGCGCUGCCUGGGCAUUGUUGGUGCUCAGGUGGCCCUAGAAGAGGCUGUGUGGCUGGAUGGACUUAGUCUCCUUCCCUUGGCACUGGCAGCGGACAUCCCUGUACGGUAUGAAAGCAGUGACACUGACAAUGCAGAGGUGGAGCCUGUUGGAAGAAAAGAGACCAGGUCUCAGCUUGACUAUGAAGUUCCCAGGGAAAAGGCCUUCCAAAAGAGCAGCACCGGCUUUUCACCUGAGACUUCCUUCCUGGAUAGCCAGGUGAUGACUGCUCUGAAGAUGGAGAGAUACCUGAAGAAGAUCCACUUCCUCUAUCUCAAUGUGGCUCCCAGCCGGUACUUUAGGCCUUACAGCCUGAUGGUGGUGCCACCCGACAAGGUGAAUCCCGAGCACUACAUCUUCUCUCCCUUUGGGAUCUUGCAUGUACAUCCUGUGGAAGGUAGCGAGACGAUGACACUGGGUACCUGGCACCAUCACUGUGUUCUCUGGCAGCAGCUCCAGUUCAUUCCAUUCUUUAAGUAUUGCCUCUUACGCAAGUCCUUUACCUGUUGGAAGAAGAAUGUGAGAUUACAGGGGCUGCAUCGACUCCAGAAAUUCCUAGAGAAUCAUCUGCUCUUGGCUGUGCCCCACUUUGGAGCUGGGCUACUCCAUAUUAGCAGGCUUCUGCAGGAGCUACACUCUGUGUCCUGGCUACCCCAGGAACUGGAUCGGUGCUAUGAGCUGCUGGACCUGCAGACGGCUCUAGCCGAGGAGAAGCAUAAGGCUCUACGGCUGCUCCAUCGUUGCCUAAACCUCUGCACAUCCAUUCUUCGACUGGUUCACGAGGACACAUACCACAUGCAACAGUGCCUACAGGAGCGAGUACAAAACUGUGACAGGAUCAGGACAGGCCAAGGCUCCAUAUACCUUCAGAGGGUACAGCACAAGCAACUGGAGCAGAAGCUGAAGCAAGCAGAGGCCUGGUGGCUGCAGCUGGGAAAGUUUGCCCGCCUGGUUGACUACAUGAUUUGUCAGAGCCUCAUUUCUGUCUUGGAAGAGCAGAUAACCUCUUUUGUGGCCAACAUCCUUCAAGCCCCAAGGCAGAAACCCUUUCUCUCAUCACAGCUGGUCUUUGAUGAUCAUGGUCAACUGUCUCAUGUGCCCUGUGUUGAAAAUAUGAUCCAGACUCUAACUGGAGGCCUACAGUCUGUCAAGACCUCUGCCUUGCAGGUAGUGCAGUCUGCAGACCUGAAGACCUCCUCGGAUUCCCUGUAUUCUGAAGAAGAAGAUGAAGAGGAGGACUCAAAAGACGAAUUUCUGAUGCCCAAGUUCCAGGGCCAGCCCAGCGAUGCUGUGAGCAUCUUCUGUGGCCCGAAUGUGGGAUUGGUGUGGCCCUGGAAGUCUCACCCAAUUGCUGGUAUCUUGGAGGUCCGUGGAUGUCGGCUGCGGGGCCAAUACUUCCCCCACAAUUAUAAGCAGCUGGAGGAAGACCUGGACAACAACCCUAAGAUCCAGCAGGCACUGAAUAUACAACAGGUGCUGCUGGAGGGCGUGCUGUGCAAGGUGCAGGAAUUCUGCAGGGAACAUCAUUGGAUAACAGGCAUUUAUGAAUUCCUGCAAUCCUGGGGGCCUCAGAAGCUGGAAGACAUGAGAGGUGGUCCCAUCAAGAACUACGUGACGCUGGUGAGCCGCCUGAAUGUUUGGCAGGCCCGUGUCUCCAGUAUGCCUAUCGAGUUGCUCACAAAAGGCGGGUUGCUGCUACUUAGCUGCCAUGAUGUACAGGCAGAGAUGGAAUCCAAGCUGAACAGCAUAAGGAAGGACAUUCUUGCACACGUGCAAAAUGAGUGCUGGAACCUCAGUCAACAACUCAUGACAGAGCUCACAGAUUUCAUGCAUAUCUUCCGAACCAUCAACUCAGAUAUUCAUGCCAUUGCACAGUGCACCCAGAAGUUGAAUGAAGCCAAUGAACAGUACGUCGAGCUGGAGGAGCGAAUGGAAUACGUACGGGCACUCCACGAACUCAUCCGCAACCACUUUAGCCUCUUUAGUGCUGAGAAUGAAGCACUGGACAUCUCGGUGAGAAGGCAAUUCGGGGAGUCACCCAUCCCUCCCUGCCCUCCUCCCCCACAACCACAUCUACUCCACUGCCCUCUGCUUGCCCCACAGCUUCUGGAUAUGUGGGAGGCAUUUCAGUUUGAGAAAAGCCAGGCUUCAGAGUUCCUGCUCAGCAAGCGACAUGCCAUUAUGCCCAAGCUGCAGCAGCUGAUGGCAGCAGCAUUGGCAGAGCUGGAAGGCCUGCUUGCGAAGGCCCUCUCCGGUCCCUUUAUGGACCCCACACAAGAUCAGAGGAGUACUGAGCACCAGCUCGUCUCCCUAGAGCGUCAGUUCCAGAACACAGUCAGCGACCUCAGUGAACUGCACCACGCCUAUGCCAUCUUCACUGAGGAUGAGACUCCUGUGCCCUUGCCAAUCUGUGGGACACGUCCUAUUGUGCAGCAGCAGCGCAUAUGGCACCUGUACCGAGUCAUCUCCGAAAACAUCAGCGAGUGGAAGUGCAUGGCUUUUGCCAAGUUCAGCCCAGCUAUGGCCCAGGAGAAGACAGAGGGCUGGCUGACAGAGGCAGCACGGAUGAGCACAACCCUGGAGCUGCACAGCCCCGUGCUGCAGCACUGCAUGCGCAUCCUGGGGGAGUUUCGCAGCUACCUGCCCCUGCUCACUAAGCUGGGCAGCCUCCACCCACAGAGCCUCAACUGCCAGUGUCUCCUGCGUGCCCUUGGGCUGGGCAGUCUCCAAACUAUAGAACUCCUAACGCUGGGCCAGCUGCUUACUUAUCCACUGCUGGAGUUUGCAGAUCGAAUCAACCAGGUCUGGCAGAAUGAAAAUGAACGAAUUCAUGCCCAAGAGACUAUACGGCGGUUGCAGCGGUACUGGGAAGCGCGCCAGCUGCGCCUGCUCAACUUCAUCCUGCAUGUACCCUACGAGCCCCCAGCCUCAGAGCGCUCCAAGAGGCAGGUGCUCCGCAGCCCCCAAUGGGAGGUAGUGGACAAAGAUAGUGGCACCUUCAUCCUCUCAGAUUACAGCAACCUGCAGGAUUCCAUCCAGGAAAGUCUUCAGGUGUUGUCCAAGAUCUUGGCCAUCGAAAAGUCAGGAGAUUUAAACAAAAUAGCUUUGGAGUGGGUGGCCAUCAUGCAUGGCCUGGGUGCCCUGCUGGAGGUGUGGCUGACUUUCCAGCAGAAGUGGAUUUUUCUGAAUAAAGUUCUGCAUGAGAUGAAGAUCCAGUUUCCUAAUGCUGACCUGAACUCUCGUUUCAAGGUCAUGGAUGACCAGUAUCGAACCCUGAUGCGCAUCUCUGUAGCUGACCCCAUGGUUCUGUCACUUGUAGUGCCCAGUGCCGAGAGGAGCCCUUACUUCCAAGGCCAGCAGCUGCAACAACUGCUGCAAGCAGGAUCGGUGGAGCUGGAGGGCAUCAUCAUGAGUCUGGAGAGCGUGCUCUAUGGGGUGUGUGCUCACUUCCCCCGCCUCUUCUUCCUUAGUGACAGUGAGCUGGUAGCCCUGCUGGCUGCUCGACUGGAAUCAUGCGAAGCCCAGCUAUGGGUACGACGCUGCUUUCCUCAUGUGCAUGCUGUGAGCUUCAGGUCUUGCCCAACUGGUGAGAAAAACACAGAUGACUGGGAGUCAAGCCCAAACACACAGACUCAGGUGGAGGCACUUGCAGUGCUAGGGGCAGGUGGGGAGGAGGUGAAGCUGCAGGGUCCCCUUCCUCUGCAUCCAGAUCUCCCUAAGUGGCUGGCCUCUCUGGAGAAGUGUCUGCGCUUGGCACUGGUGCACAUGCUGCAGGGCUGUGUGGCUGCUCGCCUUGCUCGAGGCCCAUCUCUAGGUGAGGCCCUCAAGCAACUGCCCAAGCAAAACAAGUUGUACCUGCAACUGUAUGUCCAGCACUGGAUCGACUUAGUCCAGGCCUUCCCAUGGCAGUGUGUGCUGGUGGCAGAGGAGGUGGUAUGGCGGGCCGAGAUGGAGGAGGCUCUGCUUGAGUGGGGUACCCUGGCCAUGGUCUCCAUGCAUAUGCGCAAGCUUGAGGUACUGGUGAAUUUUAUGCGGGCCCAGAGGGCUUCCCAAGGUGGGCAGUCCCUGCCUUCUGUCCGCCAGACCAGCCUUCUCAGUGCCCUGCUGGUCAUGGCAGUGACUCACCGGGAUAUAGCACAGCUGCUGGAACAGCACCAGGUCAGUGAUCUCACAGACUUUCACUGGGUCCGCCAACUCAAGUAUCACUUGGGUUCACCUCACAUAAUCCCCAAAAGCCCCCUACAGAGUCUUAAGACUAUUGCAUCUUCUGAACCCUCUCUGUCACCAGCGGCAUGCUGGAUAGAUGUGCUAGGCAGGUCCUUCCUGUACAAUUACGAGUAUCUGGGACCUAGACUAGGGCCUCUACCCAGCCUACUGCCUGAACGGCCAGCCCUGGUACUAUUAUUGGCCCUAGAGGAGGUGGCCUGUGGGACCGUACUGGGUCCUAAUGGUGUGGGCAAGAGAGCUAUAGUGAACAGCCUGGCACAGGCCCUGGGCCGCCAGCUGGUGAUGCUACCCUGCUCACCUCAGAUAGAGGCUCAAUGCCUGAGCAACUAUCUGAAUGGUGCCCUGCAGGGUGGUGCCUGGCUGCUGUUGGAGAAAGUUCAUCAGCUGCCCCCUGGCUUGCUCUCUGCCCUGGGCCAGCGCCUGGGUGAACUGCACCACUUGUAUGCCCCACUGUACCAGGAGGCUUCCCGAAACACAAGCACCAUAGACCCCACCCAGCCCCAGCUCCUUGGCAGUAGCUUCUUUGAAAAACAUCACGUGUCUGUGCGCCUUGGCUAUGGCUGUCUCCUGGUACUGCGUGCCCUGAGCUCUGCUGUGCCUGCCAACCUGCACCUGCUGCUGCGGCCUGUGGCAUUGGCAUUGCCUGAUCUGCGGCAAGUGGCAGAGCUGACUCUGCUGGGUGCAGGGAUGAGGGAUGCCUUCCAGAUGGCUACCCGCCUAUCCAAAUUCUUCUCUCUAGAGCGUGAGCUGGUGUCUGGGCCCCUGCCCUGCCGCCUGCCACUGCUCAAGCAGAUACUGGAAGACACAAUACGGACACUAAAUGUGACCAAGGAGGAACCGAAGUGCCAGAAGCCUCGCAGCCUAGCUGCCAUUGAGGAGGCUGCCCUACUGCGCUCACCACUGUUUAGCAUUCUCAAUGGGCUCCACCUGCACAACCUCCGAGGGCUGUUGUGUGCGCUUUUCCCUAGCGCCAGCCAAGUGCUGGCAGAACCUAUGACUUACAAGCUGAUGAAGCCAUUGGUGGUGGAGGAACUGCAACAGGUAGGUCUGGAUCCCAGCCCUGACAUUUUGGGGUCCUUGGAACAGUUGAGCCAGGCCCUGAGCCGGGCCUCAGGCAUUCUGCUCCUGGGCCCUGCGGGCAGCGGCAAGACCACUUGUUGGCACAGCUUAUUUAAGAUCCAGAAUCGGCUGGCAGCCAUGGAGGACACCUCAACCCAAGGCUGCCAGCCUGUGGAAAUUACCCACCUGUACCCCAGUGGCCUCAGCCCCCAGGAGUUCCUGGGAUGGCUAGAGGGCUCCUGCUGGCAUCAUGGCAUCUUUCCCAAGGUACUUCGUGCAGCCGGUCAGUGUAACAACAUGGGCCAAAAGAGGCAGACAGAGGAAUCAAUCGGGAUCCAGCACUGGAUAAUAUGUGAUGGAGCCUCCAAUGGUGCUUGGCUGGACUCCAUCACUUGCCUCCUGAGUGAGCUUCCCCAGCUUAGUCUCCCCAGUGGACAGCAGAUAGCACGACCCCCAGGCACCUUUCUCUUGAUGGAGGUGGCUGACACAACAGGCAUAUCCCCCACAGUGGUAGGCUGUUGUGCCCUAGUCUGGUGUGGUGGAGAGCAGACUUGGCAGUGUAUACUUAGUGCCCUGAUGGCAUCCCUUCCUUAUGAGUACCGCCUGCAGCACCGGACAGUCGCUGAGCUCAACCACAUGGCUGAGGUUCUGGUGCCUGCAACAUUGCGAUUCCUCACCUGCCAAGGUGUCAGCUCUCUGCUGCAGGUACACGGGCAGCAGGCUGUUUGUGCAGGUGUGGCAGAAGUUACCAGCAUGGCACGCAUCUUGCAUAGUCUGCUUGACCUCCACCUUCGCCUAAAGGAGGAGAAGGCCCCUGGCCCAGAGGACCUCAGCUAUAGUGAUCCUGUGGCCCAAAGCUUCAGGUCUUCAAAAAGCAGCUUUCUAAACCGGUCCCAGGUUGACAGUGACGAUGUGCCAGAUAAGUGCAGGGAACACUUGCUGGCUGUCAGCAGUUUUCUUUUUGCCUUGAUCUGGGGCUUUGGAGCCCACCUUCCCUCCAGGUUCUGGCCCAUCUUUGAUACCUUCAUAAGGGAUUCUAUUAGUCGCCUCUCCAACUACCCUGAGCCACCACCCUCAGCCUUGGUGUUUGAUCUACAUGUAAGCCCUGAAGAUGGAACACUGGUCCCCUUCACUGGCCAAUACCUGAGCAGCCACAUCAAAGGAACUUUGGGCACCUUUCACCCUUCUAUCCAGACUGAACGGCUCUUGUAUGUGGUGGACCUGCUUCUGUCAGGGGGACAGCCAGUGUUGCUGGCUGGAGAGGCAGCAACAGGGAAGUCAGCCUUUGUGGAGGUGCUGGUAGAGCCACAUCACCCUUACAUAUACAGCCCCAUCCACCCUGCCUUCAGUUCCUCCCACCUCCGUCUCCUGCUGAGCAGAGGAAUCCAGGGCCAAACACAAGCCAGCCCACAGCCUGGGCAUCACCAGGAUUCUAAACCCUCCCUCCUCUUCUUGCUGGAGGACCUGCACCUAGCCACUUCUGACCCAGAGAAGAGCUGCCAGCCAGUGUUGGAGACUCUGCGCCAGGCCAUGGAUGGCACUGUGUAUGCCCACAGCACCUUGGAACUGCAGACGCUGCAGCCUACAGUCAACUUCCUUGCCACUGUCACAGUGCCAGGAUACUGUGAGCGCCCACUGUGUCCACGCCUCUUUCGACUCUUCACAGUCCUGGCCCUGGAAAGCAUGACCCAGGCCACCCUGCUGGAAAGACAUGUGCCUAUCAUUCAGGCUUGGCUUGAGCGUUUCCCUUCUGUGGAACGGGAGCGUGCUCUGGCACGAGGUCUGGUUAGGGCCUCAGUAGAGGCCUGGGAGGCUGUGUGCAAUUGCUUCAUGCCUUCACCCCUCCACCCACACUACCACUUCUCCCUACACUCUGUGAGCCACCUACUGAGCAGCCUGCAGCUGCUGCCCAACAGAACAGGCUCCCGAGGUUUUGUGGACUAUCCCAACCACCAGGAGCACUUGCGCCGGGUGUCAGGCCUGCGAGGCACUUGUCUGACCGUUAUGAUGGCCACACGCAAUGUGGUGCGUCUUUGGUUGCAUGAGGCACAGAGAACCUUUUGCGACCGGCUGGACAGCCCCAGGGAACGCUCCUACUGUGCCAAGCUGCUCCUAGUAGUAGCUCAAAGUGUCUUCUGCUGUGGGCCAGGGCCCCAGCACCUGGGCAAGGACCAUCAGGAGAGUGAGGAGGAGGAGGAGGAGGAGAGGGUGCCCGAAGUAGAAUCUGAAGGGGAGUUGGCCCAGUGGGAGGACUUCAGCAACAGCAAUAGUGAAACAGAGGAGGAAGAGGAACCUUAUGGCCUUCAGGUCGCCAGAGUCUCAAACUCCAGAGAUCCAAGUCUAACACCAUCCAUAGGACCAGUAAGCAGGGGGAUGAAGGAAAGCAUAAGUCACAAGAUAAGGCAAGAGAAAGGCACAAGGGCAUCCAACUAUAGGCUCCAGGUAAGGAGAUCAUUCAAGACUUGGUGGCAGAAGAAACCCCAGAUGGACCUGAUCUCACCCUUGUUGUUACCAGUGUUACUACUACAUCCCCAGGAAAAGCCCUCAGACCUGGUCUUCAGUCAGGAGCUGAUACUGGGGCCUAACUCUGAGACCCCCAACUUGUACCUGGAACGACAGUGGGAGAAGCUAGAGGAGCAGUUGGCCACCUCAGCUGCUCAACUGAAGUUGAGCCCCCACCUGGCCCGGUGUCAUUCCAUGGCCCAGCACGUGGCCCGCCUGGUCCGGGUGCUGGCCAGGCCCCGGCAGCAUGGCCUGCUGCUCUCGGGGGCUCUGGGUACUGGGCGCCACACUGCCAUCACUCUGGCUUCUAGCAUUUGUCAGGCCCAUUUCUUUCAUCUACCAUCUGGGUCAGAGGAGGCCAUUCUCCAAUGUCUACGAGAUGCCAGCUGGCAUGCUGGCAUGUUAAGCCAGCCAGUGGCUCUGUUGGUACCCAGUGGUGUGGAUCUCACUACACUUCAUCGCCUCCUGGCCCUGGCAACCUCAGGCAGUUUCCCUGGCCAGUACACAGAAGCAGAUUUGGACCGCAUUGGAGAACACCUCCCCAGGGAGAACCUUGGUGUCAAACAGAACAUCAAGAAGGAAAUGGUGUUGCAGAGGUUCCACCAGCAAGUGUGCAGCCACCUUCACCUGUUCUUCCUGAUUGGAGAUAAACAGGCCCACAAGCAGCUGCCCUCCACCCUUUUCCUGAGGCUCCUUCAACUGGCCACUGCCAGCAUUGACCGCUAUGAACCCUGGGACCAAGCUGCCCUGGCCAAGGUGGCCCAGCAUCACCUGGAGGGUGCUCAGAGUGUGCCCCUUGAUGACGGCUCCUGGAAGUACCCAGACCUCCAGGCCUCAAUUCCCAGUGUGGCCAAAGCCAUGGCUCUUAUCCACCUUUCGGCCACCCACUACCAUGAGCACCUGUGCCCUGCAUUGCCACUCGUCACCCCCAAGACCUUCCUAGACUUCCUGGACACUUUCCUGAUGCUGCAGCAACAGACAAUCCUGAAGAUUAAGAACAAGGCCCAGCGGGUCCAGAAUGCCUUGGAGAAUCUGAGAAUGCUGAUUAAGGAGCACGGUACCCAUGCCAAUCUGAUCUUUGACUUGGAACAGCAGCUGAAAGACUCCGGCAAGAGUCUCAGCAUGUUUCAGCAGCAGCUAGAGCAAAGCAAGCUCCUAUACAAGCAGCAGCUGGAAGAGUGUCGGCAUCAAGAGAACCUCAUUGAGAACCUGGCCAGGCAACGGGAUGCCCUGCAAGCUCAGCGAGAGGCUUUCCUGGAGCAGAUGAGCAAGGCAUUUCUGGAGCCUCUGAGCCAGCUGCAGGUGGCUGACUUUGAGGAGAUACGGAGCUAUCGAGCACCACCAGAAUCUGUGGUCCGGGUAACUGAUGCAAUGUGUGACUUGUUCCACCAUGAAACAGGCUGGGCCAGUGCCAAACAGCUGUUAUGCACUGAGGAUUUUUAUCAGGAGCUGGUGUUCUUCCCCAAGGAGAAGAUAACAGACUCAGAGCUGAUAAAGUUACAUCUAAUUCUGAAGGCUCCAGGUAUGGACGAUGCAGCCCUGCGGGCAGUGAGCCGACCUGCAGCCAGCCUGGCAGCCUGGCUCUGGGCUGUUCUGCACUAUGGGCUGGCGCAUUGCCGGGGACUGCCCACGGACCUGCUGCUGCAGCAAGUGGAGGCAACACUCACUCGGGAGCAGGCCCGCCUGGGCUACUACCAGUUUCAGGCCCAGGAGACCCUGGAGCAUAAUUUGGCCCUGGCUAAGAUGGUGGAGGAUGCCCAAGCUUCCCACAACUGCGUGGCAAAGACCCUCAGUCAAGCACAGUGUGGGCAGUAUCACAAAUGGCCCAUGAAGGCUGCACUGCUCACGCCUAUGCGUGCCUGGACUACACAGCUCCAGAAGCUGAAGGGACGCUGCAUGACUGUGUUUGGAGAUACCCUCCUAUGUUCAGCUGCCAUCAUCUACCUGGGUCCCUUCCCACCAUUGCGGCGCCAAGAGCUACUGGACGAGUGGUUAGCUCUGUGUAGGGGCUUUCAGGAGGCUCUGGGCCCAGAUGAUGUGGCACAGGCACUGAAGCGGAAGCAAAAAUCUGUCAGCAUACCACCAAAGAACCCCCUGCUGGCUACACACUCUCCCUUCAGUAUUCUGUCCUUGCUGAGCUCUGAAUCGGAGCAGUACCAGUGGGAUGGAAACCUGAAGCCACAGGCAAAGUCGGCCCACCUGGCAGGCUUGCUUCUGCGAAGCCCCACACACUACAGUAGUUGCCGUUGGCCUCUGCUGCUUGACCCCAGCAACGAGGCCCUCAUCUGGUUGGACCCGCUGCCUCUGGAAGAGAAUCGAUCUUUUGCGCCAGCCCUCACUGAGGGUAGAGGGAAAGGCCUCAUGAGAAAUCAAAAGAGAGAGAGUAAAACGGACAUGAAAGAGGAAGAUGAUGAGAGUGAAGAGAGUAAUGAGGCUGAGGACCAGACAAAAGAGCAGAAGGCAGAGGAAAGAAAAAAUGAGCAGGAGAAAGAGCAAGAGGAAAAUGAAGAGAAAGAGGAGGAGAAGACAGAGAGCCAGGGGUCAAAGCCAGCCUAUGAGACUCAGCUUCCAUCCCUUCCCUACCUUAGUGUUCUUUCAGGUGCUGACCCAGAGCUGGGUUCUCAGCUCCAGGAGGCAGCUGCUUGUGGCCUGCCUGUGUUACUGACCAAUGUGGAGCUGGGUCUAGGGUGCGAAGAACUGCAAUGGCUGCUGCAACGGGAGCAGCUGAGUCCACCCCAGGUGCAGCCUGGCUUCUGUCUGUAUCUCAGCACCACCCUCUCCCUCUGUGCCAUGGAAAAAGUGCUAGGUUGUGAACUGCUAAAGGGGCUGAAUGUGUUGGAUCUGGGCCUGAACAUGGAAAUACUGGAAGAACAGAUGCUGCAUGAAAUCUUGUGCAGAGAGUAUCCUGAACUCGAGACCCGCUGGCAGGACCUAAAGAUCAGAGCCCUAGAUACCUGCAAGGCUGUGGAGGCUGCUGAGGAGCGGCUGCUGACGAUGCUGCUGUUCCAGAAUCCGAAGCGUCAGAAGCCAGCCAAGUUUCUGCGGAACAUAGUGAGGGCCCAAGGAAAGCUAUGCCAGCUGCGUGCUCAUUGUGAAGAGUUAGAAGGGCAGAAACUACAGGAGAUGGUAUUGUGGGCACCCUAUCGACCUGUGGUUUGGCAUGGAAUGGCCAUGGUAAAGGCCCUAAGCCAACUGCAGAACCUGCUGCCACUUUUCUGUAUGAGCCCAGAGAACUGGCUGGCAGUCACUAAGCAGGCUCUGGACAGCAUGAAGCCACGUGAGAUUAAUCACGGGGAGGACCUGGCCAGCCAUCUACUGCAAUUGAGAGCACACCUGACCCGCCAGCUGCUGGGCAGCACCGUGACUGCACUGGGCCUUACCCAAGUACCCUUGGUGGGUGCAUUGGGCGCUUUGGCUCUGCUGCAAGCAACAGGGAAAGCAUCAGAGCUGGAAAGACUGGCACUCUGGCCUGGACUAGCAGCCUCUCCCAGCACAGUCCACAGCAAGCCAGUCUCAGAUGUGGCUCGACCGGCCUGGCUUGGGCCAAAAGCCUGGCAUGAAUGUGAGAUGUUAGAGCUGCUGCCCCCAUUUGUUGGCCUGUGUGCCUCCCUGGCAGGCCACUCCAGUGCUUGGCAGGCUUACCUGUCACUGUCAUCCACAGUGCUGGGUCCUGCACCUGGGCCAGGGCCUGAGCCACUCAGCCUCCUCCAGAAGCUGAUCCUGUGGCGCGUUCUGCGACCUGAGUGCCUGGCAGGUGCCCUGGCAGACUUCACCACUAGCCUCCUGGGUCGGCCCCUGGAUGAAAACACGUAUGCUCCCACCAUGCCCUUUAAACAUAGUCAGGCUACUCAGCCCAUGCUGAUCUUGUUGCCACCGCCUGGCCACCCCUCAGCCACUCUGCAUCCUCUGACUGUCAUCCAGAAACUGGCUGCCAAGUAUCAGCAGGGGCAGAAGCAACUGCAGGUGAUAGCCCUGGGCUCUGAAGCCUGGGACCCAGUCUCAGUUGUGGUCAGCACUCUAUCCCAGGCUAUGUAUGAGGGGCACUGGCUGGUGCUGGACAACUGUCAUCUGAUGCCCCAUUGGCCGAAAGAGCUGCUACAGCUCUUGCUGGAACUGUUAGGCAGAGCCAAGGUGGUUGCAGACCUGGAAUCAGAACAGCUUUUAGACCAACCUGAAAGCAGGAAUGUAAGCACUGUUCACAGAGAUUUUCGUCUUUGGCUUAUUGUGCCUGCAGAGUCUAGUGCUUCUUUGCCAGCUGUGCUGACUCAGCACUCCAUGCCUGUUUUCUGGAACCAGUCCCUGGAGCUGGGCCAUGUUUUGAUUGACAGUGUGGAGCUAGCCCAGCAAGUACUCUACAUGCAACCCCCCACCCAGGCACUACCUCUGCUCCUCCUCCAUGGCCUCCUGCUACACCGGCAGCUCUAUGGAACAAGGCUGCAGGCACACAGGGGGCGCUGGAGUCAAGUGACUCUAACCCAGGUUCUUCAGACCCAAGACCAGCUGUGGGCAAGUCUUAGCAAUCCCCGUGCUGCCAUGCAAGAGCUGGCUGCUUCAGUUUUCUACGGGGGUCCUCUGGGGGACACUGAGGACAGGGAGGCCCUGAUUAGCCUCACACAAGCCUGCCUGAGCCCCAGUAGUGGGAGCUGGGUCCAGCCACACACACCUCAGUCUUUGCUGGCCACGCUCAUGCCCCUCCCAGAGCUAAGGGAGCUGGAUGCAAUGGCAGAGUGCAAGGCCCAGAUGCACCUACUGCCCUCACCACCUGAACCCCGGCUCUGCGGACUGAGUGAGGGCCCCCAAGCCUGGCUGUUGCGACGCCAGAGUCGCGCUCUCUUGAGUGCGCUGCAGCGGAGUUCACCCGUGUGGGUUCCUGAGUCUCGAAGAGGCGCCCAGCUUGCGGAAAGGCGACUGCGGCAACGCCUAGUGCAAGUCAACCGGAGGCUGGAGUCACUGCAGGAUCUGCUGACCCACGUGAUUCGCCAAGACGAGUCCGACGCCCCGUGGUCAGUGCUGGGGCCAAAUGCACGGCGGCCUCUGGAGGGCGUCUUAGAGACCGAGGCUCUAGAACUGAGCCAGUUGGUGGGCACGCUACAACGCGACCUUGAUUGCCUGUUGCAGCAGCUGAAGGGCGCACCCCCGUGCCCCUCCCGCCGCUGUGCUGCGGUGGCCCACGCUCUCUGGACUGGCCGCCUACCCUUGCCUUGGCGACCUCAUGCGCCGGCCGGUCCGCAGCCGCCCUGGCACUGGCUGCGACAGUUGUCGCGCCGUGGGCAACUGUUGGUUCGUUACUUGGGCGUGGGCGCGGACGCGAGCAGUGAUGUACCAGAGCGCGUCUUCCACCUGUCAGCCUUUCGCCACCCGCGCCGCCUGCUGCUGGCAUUGCGUGGGGAAGCUGCCCUGGACCAGAAUGUGCCCAGCUCGAAUUUCCCUGGUAGCCGAGGCUCGGUCUCCAGUCAGCUCCAGUAUAAACGUCUGGAGAUGAACAGCAACCCUCUGCACUUCAGGGUGGAGAAUGGUCCAAAUCCCACGGUUCCAGAGAGAGGGCUGCUGCUGAUCGGGCUACAGGUCCUACAUGCGGAGUGGGACCCAAUAGCUGGAGCCUUGCAGGACAGUCCUUCCAGCCAACCCAGCCCUCUGCCUCCCGUCAGCAUCAGCACACAGGCCCCGGGCACCAGUGACCUGCCAGCCCCAGCCGACCUGACUGUGUACUCGUGUCCUGUGUACAUGGGAGGGCCCCUUGGCACCGCUAAGCUGCAGAGCAGGAACAUCGUGAUGCAUCUGCCUUUACCCACCAAGCUCACCCCCAACACCUGUGUCCAAAGGAGGGUCCAUGUGUGCAGCCCACCCCUGUCUUGAGCCCGUCUACCAAAAUAAAGUUGUAGUGAUUCCA